CUAGUUCCAGUACAGCGUGGAGGGUUUAGGCAGCGUGUUCUGAUUCUUUGCGGGACGGCGAGCGCAUUUGUGCUUUGCCCGCCGCGGCCUAGGAGGCCUUUUGAGGCCGCGUAGUCGGUGUUUUUGAACUGACUCUACAGCUUCUGGCAGGCCGUGCGGCGCCCUGACCCGGCCUCACCAUGUUGGUGCUGUUUGAAACGUCUGUGGGUUACGCCAUCUUUAAGGUUCUAAAUGAGAAGAAACUUCAAGAGGUUGAUAGUUUAUGGAAAGAAUUUGAAACUCCAGAGAAAGCAAACAAAAUAGUAAAGCUAAAACAUUUUGAGAAAUUUCAGGAUACAGCAGAAGCAUUAGCAGCAUUCACAGCUCUGAUGGAGGGCAAAAUCAAUAAGCAGCUGAAAAAAGUUCUGAAGAAAAUAGUAAAAGAAGCCCAUGAACCGCUGGCAGUAGCUGAUGCUAAACUAGGAGGGGUCAUAAAGGAAAAGCUGAAUCUCAGUUGUAUCCAUAGUCCUGUUGUUAAUGAACUUAUGAGAGGAAUUCGUUCACAAAUGGAUGGAUUAAUCCCUGGGGUAGAACCACGUGAAAUGGCAGCUAUGUGUCUUGGAUUGGCUCACAGCCUGUCUCGAUAUAGAUUGAAGUUUAGCGCUGAUAAAGUAGACACAAUGAUUGUUCAGGCAAUUUCCUUGUUAGAUGACUUGGAUAAAGAACUAAACAACUACAUUAUGCGAUGUAGAGAAUGGUAUGGCUGGCAUUUCCCUGAAUUAGGAAAAAUUAUUUCAGAUAAUUUAACAUACUGCAAGUGUUUACAGAAAGUUGGCGAUAGGAAGAACUAUGCCUCUGCCAAGCUUUCUGAGUUGCUGCCAGAAGAAGUUGAAGCAGAAGUGAAAGCAGCUGCAGAGAUAUCAAUGGGAACAGAGGUUUCAGAAGAAGAUAUUUGCAAUAUUCUGCAUCUUUGCACCCAGGUGAUUGAAAUCUCUGAAUAUCGAACCCAGCUCUAUGAAUAUCUACAAAAUCGAAUGAUGGCCAUUGCACCCAAUGUUACAGUCAUGGUUGGGGAAUUAGUUGGAGCACGGCUUAUUGCUCAUGCAGGUUCUCUUUUAAAUUUGGCCAAGCAUGCAGCUUCUACCGUUCAGAUUCUUGGAGCUGAAAAGGCACUUUUCAGAGCCCUCAAAUCUAGACGGGAUACCCCUAAGUAUGGUCUCAUUUAUCAUGCUUCACUCGUGGGCCAGACAAGUCCCAAACACAAAGGAAAGAUUUCUCGAAUGCUGGCAGCCAAAACCGUUUUGGCUAUCCGUUAUGAUGCUUUUGGUGAGGAUUCAAGUUCUGCAAUGGGAGUUGAGAACAGAGCCAAAUUAGAGGCCAGGUUGAGAACUUUGGAAGACAGAGGGAUAAGAAAAAUAAGUGGAACAGGAAAAGCAUUAGCAAAAACAGAAAAAUAUGAACACAAAAGUGAAGUGAAGACUUACGAUCCUUCUGGUGACUCCACACUUCCAACCUGUUCUAAAAAACGCAAAAUAGAACAGGUAGAUAAAGAGGAUGAAAUUACUGAAAAGAAAGCCAAAAAAGCCAAGAUUAAAGUUAAAGUUGAAGAAGAGGAAGAAGAAAAAGUGGCAGAAGAAGAAGAAACAUCUGUGAAGAAGAAGAAGAAAAGGGGUAAAAAGAAACACAUUAAGGAAGAACCACUUUCUGAGGAAGAACCAUGUACCAGCACAGCAAUUGCUAGUCCAGAGAAAAAGAAGAAAAAGAAAAAAAAGAGAGAGAACGAGGAUUAACAGAAAGGAAUUACGAUUAUAUCACCCGGACACACAUCAUGCUUAAGAUUCAACUGGGAGCAUACCAGGGAUGCUCUCUAACGUAAUCAAGGGAAGGUUCAGUAAGACAAAGUGAUUUAUCAUCUAUAACUUCAAACCUAUUUGUCUUGACAUCAACUCUGUUAACCUUAUGUCAUCAUUUCUUAGAGUCUUUGAUAUACAAAUAAAAUUUUCUUUGUAUUUUAA